GAAGACCCCGGAAGUGCAACUCGAACUUGGUCGGGGCGCGGAUCCCGAGAGGGAAAGUCAUAACAACCGCACGAGGGAGUUCGACUGGCGAACUGGAAGGCCACGCCUCCUCCCGCCUGCCCCCUCAGCCCUGUGGCUGGGGGCAGAGCUCAGGUAGGACUGCCGUUUGCGGGGAUGUGAGCUCCGGGGGCAGGCCCGGGUCGAAAUCAGGAGGGGGCUGGCCUGGGUCGGUCUCAGGCGGUGGUCGCUGGCCCUGGGGACCGAGGCUGUCUGGAACCACGCUGCAUUCCCUGCGGACACCUCUGACUUGUGUCUGGGCCUCCGCUGAUGGGCAGGUCCCAUGUUCCAUUUCCACUCUCUAGGCGGGAGCGACGUGUGUGUUCCCUGGAUGACUUUCCUUAUGUCGGGGCGUACGGGAUUCUGGGAGUCCCUGGAGACAGAGUAAUGGGCCCUCCUCCGCUUUCUUGCGAGUGGAGACUGUCUUCUGAAGAUUGAUGUCUAUUUCCUUGAGCUCUUUAAUUUUGUUGCCAAUUUGGAUAAACAUGGCACAAAUCCAGCAGGGAGGUCCAGAUGAAAAAGAAAAGACUACCGCACUGAAAGAUUUAUUAUCUAGGAUAGAUUUGGAUGAACUAAUGAAAAAAGAUGAACCGCCUCUUGAUUUUCCUGAUACCCUGGAAGGAUUUGAAUAUGCUUUUAAUGAAAAGGGACAGUUAAGACACAUAAAAACUGGGGAACCAUUUGUUUUUAACUACCGGGAAGAUUUACACAGAUGGAACCAGAAAAGAUACGAGGCUCUAGGAGAGAUCAUCACGAAGUAUGUAUAUGAGCUCCUGGAAAAGGAUUGUAAUUUGAAAAAAGUAUCUAUUCCAGUAGAUGCCACUGAGAGUGAACCAAAGAGUUUUAUCUUUAUGAGUGAGGAUGCUUUGACAAAUCCACAGAAACUGAUGGUUUUAAUUCAUGGUAGUGGUGUUGUCAGGGCAGGGCAGUGGGCUAGAAGACUUAUUAUAAAUGAAGAUCUGGACAGUGGCACACAGAUACCGUUUAUUAAAAGAGCUGUGGCUGAAGGAUAUGGAGUAAUAGUACUAAAUCCCAAUGAAAACUAUAUUGAAGUAGAAAAGCCGAAGAUACACGUACAGUCAUCAUCUGAUAGUUCAGAUGAACCAGCAGAAAAACGGGAAAGAAAAGAUAAAGUUUCUAAAGAAACAAAGAAGCGACGUGAUUUCUAUGAGAAGUAUCGUAACCCCCAAAGAGAAAAAGAAAUGAUGCAAUUGUAUAUCAGAGAAAAUGGUUCUCCUGAAGAACAUGCAAUCUAUGUUUGGGAUCAUUUCAUAGCUCAGGCUGCUGCUGAGAAUGUGUUUUUCGUUGCUCACAGCUAUGGAGGACUUGCUUUUGUUGAACUGAUGAUUCAACGAGAAGCCGAUGUAAAAAAUAAGGUAACUGCUGUGGCAUUGACAGACUCUGUUCACAAUGUGUGGCAUCAAGAAGCUGGCAAAACGAUUCGAGAAUGGAUGAGAGAGAACUGUUGUAAUUGGGUCUCUAGCUCAGAACCAUUAGACACAUCAGUGGAGUCCAUGCUACCUGAUUGCCCCCGGGUCUCAGCAGAUGAGUAAACAGAGGUUCAUGUGGUUUGUAAGUGGGGGAGUUGAGAUUCUAAUCCAGAUCUGAUAGUUGCAAACCACACUACUUCGCCGACACUCGCCAGAGAACGGCAGCACCAGAGGCAGUUCCUGAAGGUUUGCCAUGGUAGCAGCCUCUGGAAGAGGAACAGGGAAUUUGUCUUCAAGCUGUAUUGUAUACUUACAAAUAUAUUGUGUAUGUGUUUAGGGUAAUUUGGGGAAAACUAAUAAAAUUCAUGAGGAGGCCAAAGUCCCUGCACAUUUGCAAGUUAUACCUUGGUGCUUUUCCAGAAGGACUAUAUGGGAGUGAUUGUGGUAGAAAUGAAAUAAGCAGCUGAUAAAUGGGUCAUUUUUAAUUUUCAUUUUUUAUUUAAACUAUCGAUCUUUUUAUUGCAAUAAAAUGUCACAAGUAAAAAUAAAGAAUUUAUGACAGUUUUAACGUGGUGGAAGGUAGAGCAAACAAAUGGAGAAAAAAUCCAGGUGAAGGAUUAAUAAUUAAAUAAUGAAACUCUUAAACUUGAAAAUAUCUGUGAACUUUAACAAAAAUAUGUAUAAUAGAUAUGGAUGCAAAUUCCCUUUGAUGCUUACAUCUGAGAACCCAGGGAAGUGAAAGGAACAUAUUAAGAAGGAGACUUCAUAGCAACACUGGACUGAGAGUUAAGAGAAUCAAGCCCACUUCACCCCUACCCAACCCAACCCUUCCAUUAGUGGAUCUGGCUCCUUCUUUCCUUCAUUUAUUCAGAAAUGCUUAUUGAGCCCCCUGUAUGUCAGAUACUUUUCUGAAUACUAGGGAUUUGGCUAUGAAAAGGAUAAGCAAAAUUCCUUUUCAUAGCCAAAUGUAAGCUCUGUUGCAUAGAGCUUACAUUUCAGAAGAGAAAAUAGAUACUAGGUAGACAAAUCGACAUAUAAAGUUUAUGUUUUAGAUAGUGAUGUUAGGAUAAAAAUUCAGUAGGCUAAGUGGUGAGAGAGUACCUGAUGGGGCCCAGUGGUAUGUUUUAUAUAGCGUGGUCAGGAGAGGCCUCAGUGAGGAGCUCCUUGUGUUGUCUGUACCUUUUAGGACCUUAGUCUCUUCAUACAUAAAAUGAGAGCAUUGCUAGGUGAUCACUAAAUGGCUGCAAAAUUCUGUUCUUCCUUUAAGGGACAUAUCUUCGGAUCAGAUAAUCUUUUGUAUGUAUAAGUUACGGUCUUUACUGUCAACUGAUCUCAAAAUGUAAUAAGAAUGUUCAUUGAUUCCCAAGGUUAAUUCCAUUUUUACAUUUGGGGAAUUUAAACUGAGAAUAAAAUGCCUUCCCAAAGAUUGCAUAAUAGUAAAAGAAGGAUUAAAGCUCUCAAUUCCUGCCACUCUUAGUCUGAAAACGUCACCCCACCAUGUGCUAUAAUGAGAAGUUGAAUUGAAAUGUCAGGGCAGUUCAAAGUAGAUUAAAGAUGUGUAAGCUGUGAUGGACUACAUAUUUACAAAUAAGGAAUUGGAUAAGUAUAUCCCACUGCACUCAUUUACGGCAGGCAAGUAAGCCAUGUGAUAUGCUUUAAGCCAGUAAAAUAGCAAAUUCCCCCCAAAAGAUCUAUAAUUUUAAUCAAAAGUUUGUUUCAGUCAUUGAAAUUCUGUUAUUGCUGCUUACCAACAUUAAAGUCAAUCAAAACAUCAGUAGCUUUGCAAGAUCAAUAUUUUUAAUAUGUUUGCAUUGCAGUGCUGCAGAUUUUUGGCUAGUGGAUCGCACCUAUAUUGAUUUCCAUGGGAAAUGUUAGUCUGAUACUGAAAUAAUUAAAAAAAAAAACAGGGAUUAUUGGUUUGGAAUUUUGAAGGAGAUAGAACUAUAAAAAUUGGUUAUUGACUAAAUUGCUUGGGGUGAGUGAACCUUGGGCACUUGCAAUAAACUUGUAGCACUCAUUCAUUACUGAAUACUACCUUAGUCCCUUAAACUGAAAAAUCAGUCAAUAACCUAUUAUAACAAUGCAAAUUGUGGUGAAAUAACAUACUAUGCAUAUAAGAAUCACAUUUUAUCAAAACAGAUAUGCGUAAGUAUAUGUAUGGGCGUAUUGAAAGUGUCUGCUAAAACAUAGUGACUGAUUUUGACUUUGAGAUUCAUGCUGAAGCUCAUUUGAAUAGCAUUUUAAAAGAGAUAAACUGCUACAAAAUAACAGUAAAAAGAAGCAUACAAUUAUUCUAUGAACAAUAAUGAAAGUGCAAACACUACAGCACGUCAAAUGACAGAUUCUGUUAUUUUGAUUCAGAGCAAAAUUACAAUUGUUAUUCUGUUCUCAAAGCAUAGGAAUAAUGUAUGCAAGCAUUAGAUUAGAUACAAACACAUUCCCCACAAUAUGAAUCUAGUGCAUAUUACAUUGCUCUUGUUUUUCAGCAUUUGGUUAGGAGAGCCGUAUUUUCAUCUAGAAAGUUUACUCUGCGUUUUCAUUUGGUUACCAUUGUAAAUUUAUGAAUUUUUUAUCUCUCAGAGGCAAUCUAGUGUUUUACAGAGAGAGUGUUUUUAAUGUCUCAAUAAAAGUUCUAUCCAGGAUAAUAGUAAGUACUUAGGAGUACCAGUUACAUAUUUUGUUAUAUAUUUUUAUUUACUGAAUUUUAAAAUCUGUAUGUUAUUUACAUAAUAUGGAAACGUUUAUCUGCUUUGAAGGAAACGGGAAUAAGAUAAAACUAAAAAUUAGUAAUCACAACUGUUGCAUUUUGUUGCCAUCUCUAUAAGCCUGGUCAGUAUUUUCCUUUCAUAAUAAGUAGUACUCUCUUUAUAAAUAGAAAAUUGAUUAUGAUUCCUUCUGCUGCAGGAGAUAGUAACACUCAGAUAAUAGCAUUGGCAUUCUAUUUCAAUUUAGCAUUAAUCUUUGAUCACCAUUUUUUUUUCAAAAUUCCUUUAUCCUAUUCUGACUACUUUUAUCAUUAUAACUACCAUUACCCUAAAUUCAGUUGAUAAAAUCAUUUUUCUUCCUUUUCGUUUAAAAUGUAUACCUGAAUCUAACUUUUCUCUAAUAUUCUAUGUCUCCCCAUCAGUUAAGCUGUUAGGAUAUUCUGUUUUGAUGGAUUUGCCUUAGGGAUGAUUUAUGAGACAGGAAGCUUCAAUGUUAUCUAACAUUAGGUACAUCAUACCUGAAAAUAACCAAGUUGUACAGUAAAGAUAUAUGCAUGUAAGUAGUGUAAAAAUUCAUACAAUAUUUGCUAAAUCAUUCAAUGGCUUUCUGCUAAGAAUAUUAUUAGAAAAGUAUCCAUGGUCUUAAAAAUGAUAGGAUUCUAAUUCCCAAGCCUGCUGUUUCCAUAUAAUUGUAUAUAAAUAUACAAUUAUUCUUCCGUUUAUGUCUUUCUAAGAAUUUCACCUGGAAUUUGUGUUACUUAUUAUUGUCAAAAAAUGUUAUUUCCUCACCAGAUAGAAUUUGUGCAAUCCCAGUUAGAAUCUCCAGGUGUCUAACUAGUCAAGGAGCAGGACAGAGCAAAUACAUAGUUCUGCAAGGCUCCGUAGCCCACUCCUACAGCCACAUGGACCUCUGGGCCUCUGUUCUGAUCUCAUCUAGAUUUUUCAUCUAGUAUACUAGUGCCGUUUCUACCUAGAAUGGCUGUCAUCUGACAACUUUUUAGUAGUUUAGAAUUCACGUAACUUGAAACUUGGUACAGAACAUCCCUGUUGUCUUUACUGGCAGUCGCAGCAGAAACCAGGCUGUUGUCUAACUGUGAAGGUAGUGUCUGAGCACAAGCCUGAAGCUCCAGGGGAGGACAGAUUUUUACAUUUAUUUGUGGACUCUGGACAUUUGGCAAAAUCCAUUGCACUCAAUAGACAGCAGUCAAAUUAACAGGGAGAUUGUUCUCCACUUAUCGAAACUGUCAAAAAACUGAGGGAAGGGGGGAUUCCAAAGAGCUGCUCCUAGUGCAUUCUUUUUAUAUUAAUGGUUAGUGAAUACCAGUGUCAGAAGUUCACAUCACAGUACGAAUAAGAUGAUUGGAUUUUAAUUUUUAGACAAAAAUAGUCUUUCCACAUUCUAGGUCAUGCUGAUAAAAACUUUUUUGCGAACCAAACUAUUCAGAUAGUCUGUACCAAGCCUUACCUAUACGCAGCUAGAAAAUACCUAGAGGGCUUUAUUCAUUAACAAAUUAUCACACAUGCAUGCUGCUCAGAGAGUAUGUUUAAGAUAGUGGUUAAAAGCACAGGCUCUGAAGCUAUACUGCCUGAGUUUGUUUCCUUUCUGUGCCACUUUUCUAUCUCUGUAUCUAUUGUCAAGUUGCCACUCUCUCUGUACUUCCAUUCCUUCACCUGAGAACUGAUAAGAGUAGGGCUUACUACAUAGGAUGUUGUGAGGAUGUUGUACAGCAUUUAUUAUUUGGUUCUAUAUUCAGUCUAUUCUGAUAACUGUGCUGUUGGGAGCAGAAAUGAAAGACUUUAAUUUCUAGGAGUUUUAUCUCUGAAAUUCUAUCUCCUGUAACCUGGAAGAGCUUCUAUUCUCUGCCCCCAUGGCACCCUGCAUGACCCCCACCAUAGCAUAUGUUACUGUGCAGUAUCUAUUGCCUCUCCUACCUACAAUAAACUGUAAGCUUCAUGAGGACAAAAUGUGUGUCUAUCUUAUAAUCAUUAUUGCUUCAAUGCCUAACAUAUAGUUUGUACUCAGUAAAUAUUUAUUGGAUGAAUGUUAAAUAAAAUGUAAUAAAAGAAAUAUCACAAAUAUUAGAGUGUUCAUCUGUAAAAUUUUGCUUCGAUUAAAUUACUUUCCUGGUAUUAGCAGAGGCUGACAUGCAAUGAGUUAUUUCCACUUCUUUGCAUUGGCCUCUGCCUAGAAUGAACUACCCUUAGAUAACCACAGGCUCACCCCUCAUUUUCUUUGGAUCUUUGUUCAAAUAUCACCUUCUCGGUGUUUCCUAUCCUGACUGCCUCAUUUGAAACUGCAUUUCUAUCCCUUCUUCUGUUCUGUUUCAUUUUUAUAUGGCAUUUAUGGCAGUCUAGCCCUGUAUAUAUUUUAGUUAUUUGUUAUAUUUAUGAUUUGUUGGCCUCAACUUCUCCUCACUAGAAUGUAAGCUUUGUCAGUUUGGCUCACUUAUACAUCCCUAGCACCUGGAACAGUGCCUGGCACAAGGUAGACAGGCACUUUAACAAAUAUUUGUUGAAUUAAUUAAUAAAUGUAAUGCAUUGGGAAUGCCAACUUGGAAAUAACCAAAAGCAAAAUUACUAUUCAAGGAAAAUCAACAGAGAAUUAGAAACAAAAAACUUCAGGCUCCGUCUUGAGAUCAAUUAUAUACAGUUUUUUACUUGCUAAAGGUACAUACUUCAACCUCCCUGAGCCCUUUAACCCAGCCUCCAAAUUCUGAAAAUCACUCUUACCAAAAUAUUCUUCCAACGGUUAUUCUGGGGACUGUAUUGCAUUUUUUUAAUAAAAUAAUAUAUGUCUGAGACUAUAUUUUUCAAGUUAUGUAAGAUUCUAGUGUUAGAGGCAUUUUAUAAAAGGGUUAAACCCUAAAGCAAACUGCUUCUUUAAAUAUGUUAUGAACUUUCCAUAGAGCACAAAUACAAGAUCUCUGCAAGGCUUUAAUUAAGAAUAAUUAAAAUAUCUAUAUUAAAAUAUGUUUCAUUCUACCAGCUUAGUAGAGGUUUUUAUUUCAAUAAAAAAGUUUAUUUUUUACAUGUUAACAGCAUAAAACACAACAUUGCGCUCGUAACAGCAGGGAAAAUGUGAUGUGCUGAAGCGGUAAGAAACAAUGUGAUUUAUAAAUUAAUUCCCUGCAUUAUUUUUGUUAAAAAUUUUUUUCAUUAAGAUUAAACUUUCACUUUGGUGGUUAGUUGUUUGAAUUCAUUAUGCGGGCAUCAUACAAACAAAUUAAACAAGAAAAUUAUAUAAGAAGUAAAGAAGAAUUGCAUUGGGGCAAAAUAUUUUAAAAGUGUAAAGGCUUGGUGUCAUAUAUGAGGUGAGAUUUUUAUUCAGUCUGCUGUUUGUAAGAUUAUUUAACUAUUUAAUUAUGUCAUAAAAUGAGUUAAUAAGAAAGAAUGUUUAAACAAAAAAUUUAAAGAAGGCAAGCAAUUGUUACAGGGAUGGGUCAAGAGAGCCAGAUAUUGUAUGUAAUUCCCAAGCAUUCAUAAAGGGGAGAGAUAUAGAAAGGGUCAAAACCCAAAGGGAAGAGAAAACUAGUAAUUAUUAGGUCUGAUGAGAUGAACCUAUCUCAUUAAAAAAAAGAUUUGAGAAGAGAACAGAUGGGAAGAUAAGUAAACACUAAAUAAACUUGCUAAUAGGGAGAUGGAUUAUCAUUUUUCUCACUACGACGGGAAGAUCUAACUAAACUUGUCCGCCAACCUUUUUUUUUUUUUUUUUUUUUGAGAUGGAGUCUCGCUUUGUCACCCAGGCUGGAAUGCAGUGGUGCAAUCUCGACUCACUGCAACCCCUCCCUCCCAGAUUCAAGCGAUUCUCCUGCCUCAGCCUCCCGAGUAGCUGGGAUCACAGGCACCCACCAUCAUGCUUGGCUAAUUUUUGUAUUUUUAGUAGUGAUAGGGUUUCACCAUGUUGGCCAGGCUGGUCUCAAACUCUCGACCUCAGGCAAUCCACCCACCUCCGCCUCCCGAAGUGCUGGGAUUACAGGCUUGAGCCACUGCAUCCAGCCACUUGUCCUUUUUAAAAAAGACAGUAAUGUGAAGAGAGGAGAGCCAUGAAUGUGGCAGGCAUUGUGGUAUUUUUGACUCAUACCAAAAAAAACACUUCUAUCUCUUACUACUGCAUUCUCCACAUUAGUCUCAAAGACAAUGGUAAGAUCUAAGUAUUACCAAGAAUGAGUGACACAUUGAAUCAAUAACAUCCCCAUUCAUGCUCUAAUAUAAUACUUCCAGGAGAGAGGGAUGAGGAUUGCAAAGGAGCUAUUGAUCUAAGUAAUAGAGAAAUUUAGGAGAAUAUGGGAUUCUAUCUAAUCAUCAGAUCCAAUAAGACGUUCAGGGAUUGAGAAGGAGAGAUCCAUUAAACUGAACCUUGAAAGAUGGGUAGGAUUUGAAGAUUCAUAGAAGGGAAGAAGACUAUUUCAACUAGGGUUGUCAGCAUGAACUAGGGCUUGAAAGUACAGGACAUGUGACAUAAACAUUUGUAAUAGCAAAAAAGGAGGUUGACAGAUGCAUCACUGAUGUGAAUGGAGAAGGAAGAAAAUAAAAGUUAUAAGUGUGAAUGAGAUGACAGGGAACAGGCUGUCAUUGUGUUUGUGGGUUUUUUUAUAGAUACCUUAAAUUCUGGGAUACAUGUGCAGAACGUGCAGGUUUGUUACAUAGGUAUACACGUGCCACGGUGGUUUGCUGCACCCAUCAACCCGUCAUCUACAUUAAGUAUUUCUCCUAAUGCUUUCCCUCCCCUAGUCCCCCACCCCCCGACAGACCCCGGUGUGUGAUGUUCCUCUCCCUGUGUCCAUGUGUUCUCAUUGCUCAACUCCCACUUAUAAGUGAGAACAUGCAGUGUUUGGUUUUCUGUUCUUGUGUUAGUUUCCUGAGAAUUAUGGUUUUCAGCAUCAUCCAUGUCCCUGCAAAGGACAUGAACUCAUCCUUUUUUAUGGAUGCAUAGUAUUCCAUAGUGUAUAUGUGCCACAUUUUCUUUAUCCACUCUGUCACUGAUGGGCAUUUGGGUUGGAUCCAGGUCUUUGCUAUUGUGAACAGUGCUGCAGUAAACAUACAUGUGCAUAUGUCUUUCUGGUAGAAUGAUUUAUAAUCCUUUGGGUAUAUACCCAGUAAUGAGAUUGCUGGGUCAAAUGGUAUUUCUGGUUCUAGAUCCUUGAGGAAUUGCCACACUGUCUUCCACAAUGGGUGAACUAAUUUACACUCCCACCAACAGUGUAAAAGUGUUCCUAUUUCUCUACAUCCUCUCCAGCAUCUGUUGUUUCCUGACUUUUUAAUGAUCGCCAUUCUAACUGGCAUGAGAUGGUAUCUCAUUGUAGUUUUGAUUUGCAUUUCUCUAAUGACCAGUUAUGAUGAGCUUUUUUCCAUAUGUUUGUUGGCUGCAUAAAUAUCUUCUUUUGAGAAGUGUCUGUUCAUAUCCUUCACCCACUUUUUGGUGGGAUGGUUUUUUUCUUGUAAAUUUGUUUAAGUUUUUAUAGAUUCUGGAUAUUAGCCCUUUCUCAGAUGGAUAGAUUGCAAAAAUUUUCUCCCAUUCUGUAGGUUGCCUGUUCACUCUGAUGAUAGUUUCUAUUGCUGUGCAGAAGCUCUUUAGUUUAAUUAGAUCCCAUUUGUCAAUUUUGACUUUUGUUGCCAUUGCUUUCGGUGUUUUAGUCAUGAAGUCUUUGUUCAUGCCUGUGUCCUGAAUGGUAUUGCCUAGGUUUUCUUCUGGGAUUUUUAUGGAUUUAGGUCUUAUGUUUAAGUCUUUAAUCCAUCUUGAGUUAAUUUUUGUGUAAGGUGUAAGGAAGGGGUCCAGUUUCAGUUUUCUGCAUAUGGCUAGCCAGUUUUCCCAAUACCAUUUAUUAAAUAGGGUAUCCUUUCCCAGUUGCUUGUUUGUGUCAUUUUUGUCAAAGAUCAGAUGGUUAUAGAUGUGUGGUGUUAUUUCUGAGGCCUCUGUUCUGUUCCAUUGGUCAAUAUAUCUGUUUUGGUACCAGUACCGUGCUGUUUUGGUUACUGUAGCCUUAUAGUAUAGUUUGAAAUCAGGUAGCGUGAUGCCUCCAGCUUUUUUCUUUGUGCUUAGGAUUGUCUUGGCUAUGUGAGCUCUUUUUUGGUUCCAUAUGAAAUUUAAAGUAGCUUUUUCUAAUUAUGUGAAGAAAGUCAGUGAUAGCUUGAUGGGGAUAGCAUUGAAUCUAUAAAUUACUUUGGGCAGUAUCACCAUUUUCACCAUAUUGAUUUUUCCUAUCCAUGAGCAUGAAAUGUUUUUCCAUUUGUUUGUGUCCUCUCCUAUUUCCUUGAGCAGUGGUUUGUAGUUCUCCUUGAAGAGGUCCUUCACAUCUCUUGUCAGUUGUAUUCCUAGGUAUUUUAUUCUCUUAGUUGCAAUUGUGAAUGGGAAUUCACUCAUGGUUUGGCUCUUUGUUUGUCUAUUAUUGGUGUAUAGGAAUGCUUGUGAUUUUUGCACAUUGAUCUUGUAUCCUGAGACUUUGCUGAAGUUGCUUAUCAGCUUAAGGGGAUUCGGGGCUGAAACGAUGGGGUUUUCUAAAUGUACAAUCAUGACAUCUGCAAACAGAGACAAUUUGACUUCCUCUCUUCCUAUUUGAAUACCUUUAUUUCUUUCUCUUGCCUGAUCUCCCUGGCCAGAACUUCCAAUACUGUGUUGAAUAGGAGUUGUGAGAGAGGGCAUCCUUGUCUUGUGGCGGUUUUCAAAGGGAAUGCUUCCAAGUUUUGCACAUUCAGUAUCGUAUUGGCUGUUUGUCAUAAAUAGCUCUUAUUAUUUUGAGAUACAUUCCAUCAGUGCCUAAUUUUUUUAGAGUUUUUAGCAUGAAGGGGUGUUGAAUUUUGUCGAAGGCCUUUUCUGCAUCUAUUGAGAUAAUCAUGUGGUUUUUUUUCAUUGGUUCUGUUUAUGUGAUGUAUUAUGUUUAUUGAUUUGCGUCUAUUGAACCAGCCUUACAUCCCAGGGAUGAAGCAGACUACAUCGUGGUGGAUAAGCUUUUUGAUGUGCUGCUGGGUUUGGUUUGCCAGUAUUUUAUUGAAGAUUUUCGCAUCGAUGUUCAUGAGAGACAUUGGCCUGAAGUUUUCUUUUCUGUGUUGUGUCUCAGGAUGAUGCUGGCCUCAUAAAAUGAGUUAGGGAGGAUUCCCUCUUUUUCUACUGUUUCGAAUAGUUUCAGAAGGAAUGGUACCAGCUCCUCUUUGUACUUCUGCUAGAAUUCAGCUGUGAAUCCAUCUGGUCCUGGACUUUUUUUUUUGGUUGGUAGGCUAUUAAUUACUGCCUCAAUUUCAGAACUUGUUAUUUAUCUAUUCAGGGAUUUGACUUCUUCCUGGUUUAGACUUGGGAGGGUGUAAGUGUCCAGGAAUCUAUCCAUUUCUUCUAUAUUUUCUAGGUUAUUUGUGUAGAGGUGUUUAUAGUAUUCUCUGGUGGUAGUUUGUAUUUCUGUGAAAUCAGUGGUGAUAUCCCCUUUAUCAUUUUUUCUUGCAUCUAUUUGAUUCUUUAUACUUCUCUUCUUUGUUAAUCUGGCUAGCAGUCUAUUUAUUUUGUUGAUCUUUUCAAAAAACCAGCUCCUGGAUUCAUUGAUUUUUUUGAAGGGUUUUUCAUGUCUCUGUCUCCUUCAGUUCUGCUCUGAUCUUAGUUAUUUCUUGUCUUCUGGUAGCUUUUGAAUUUGUUUGCUCUUGCUUCUCUAGUUCUUUUAAUUGUGAUGUUAGGGUGUCGAGUUUAAAUCUUUCCUGCUUUCUCUUGUGGGCAUUUAGUGCUAUAAAUUUCCCUCUAAACACUGCUUUCACUGUGUCCCAGAGAUUCUGGUACAUUGUGUCUUUGUUCUCAUUGGUUUCAAAGAAUGUAUUUAUUUCUGCCUUAAUUUUGUUAUUUACCCAAUAGUCAUUCAGGAGCAGGUUGUUCAGUUUCCAUGUAGUUGUGCGGUUUUGAGUGAGUUUCUUAAUCCUGAGUUCUAAUUUGAUUGCACUGUGGUCUGAGAGAGUGUUCGUUAUGAUUUCCAUUCUUUUGCAUUUGCCAAGGAGUGUUUUACUUCCAAUUAUAUGGUCAGUUUUAGAAUAAGUAUGAUGUGGUGCUGAGAAGAAUGUAUAUUCUAUUGAUUUGGAGUGGAGAAUUCUUUCUGUAGAUGUCUAUUAGGUCUGCUUAGUCCAGAGCUGAGUUCACGUCCUGAAUAUCCUUGUUAAUUUUCUGUCUUGUUGAUCUAUCUAAUAUUGACAGUGAGGUGUUAAAGUCUCCCAGUAUUAUUGUGUGGGAUUCUAAGUCUCUUUGUAGGGCUCUAAGAACUUGCUUUAUGAAUCUGGGUACUCCUAUAUUGAGUGCAUAUAUAUUUAGGAUAGUUAGCUCUUCUUUUUGCAUUGAUCCCUUUACUAUUAUGUAAUGCCCUUUUUUGUCUCUUUUGAUCUUUGUUGGUUUAAAGUCUGUUUUAUCAGAGACUAGGAUUGCAACCCCUGCUUUUUUGUUUGCUUGUUUUGUUUUGUUUUUGUUUUUGUUUUCUUGGUAAAUAUCCCUCCAUUGUUUUAUUUUGAGCCUAUGUGUGACUUUGCACGUGAGAUGGGUCUCCCGAAUACAGCCCACUAAUGGGUCUUGACUCUUUAUCCAAUUUGCAAGUCUGUGUCUUUUAAUUGUGGCUUUUAACCCAUUUACAUUUAAGGUUAACCUUGUUAUGUGUGAAUUUGAGCCUGUCAUUAUGAUGGCUAGCUGGUUAUUUUGCCCGUUAGUUAAUGCAGUUUCUUUAUAGUGUCGAUGGUCUUUACAAUUUGGUAUGUUUUUGCAGUGGUAGGUACCAGUUUUUCCUUUCCAUAUUUAGUGCUUCCUUCAGGAGCUCUUGUAAGGUAGGCCUGGUGGUGACAAAAUCUCUUAGCAUUUGCUUAUCUGUAAGGGAUUUUAUUUCUUCUUCGCUUAUGAAGCUUAGUUUGGCUCGGUAUGAAAUUCUGGGUUGAAAAUUCUUUCAUUUAAGAGUGUUGAAUAUUGGCCCCCACAGUCUUCUGGCUUGUAGGGUUCUGCAGAGAGAUUCACUGUUACUCUGAUGGGCUUCCCUUUAUGGGUAAUCUGAUCUUUCUCUCUGGCUACCUUAACAUUUUUUCCUUUAUUUCAAUCUUGGUGAAUCUGACAAUUAUGUGUCUUGGGGUUGCUCUUCUCGAGGAGUAUCUUGGUGGUGUUCUCUGUAUUUCCUGAAUUUGAAUGUUGGCCUGUCUUGCUAGUUGGGGAAUUUCUCCUGGAUAAUAUCCUGAAGAGUGUUUUCCAACUCGGUUCCAUUCUCCCCGUCACUUUCAGGUACACCAGUCAAACGCAGGUUUGGUCUUUUCACAUAGUCCCAUAUUUCUUGGAGGCUUUGUUUGUUCCUUUUCAUUCUUUUUUCUCUAAUCUUGUCUUCAUGCUUUAUUUCGUUAAGUUGAUGUUCAAUCCCUGAUAUCCUUCCUUCUGCUUGAUCAAUUUGGCUGUUAAUACUUGUAUAUGCUUCACGAAGUUCUUGUGCUGUGCUUUUGAGCUCCAUCAGGCCAUUUAUGUUCUUCUCUAAACUGUUUAUUCUAGUUAGCAAUUCCUCUAACCUUUUUUCAAGGUUCUUAGCUUCCUUGCAUUGAGCUAGAACAUGCUCCUAUAGCUCAGAGGAGUUUGUUAUUAUCCAUCUUCUGACUCCUACUUCUGUCAAUUUGUCAAAGUCAUUCUCCAUCCUGUUUUGUUCCCUUGCUGGCCAGGAGUUGUGAUCAUUUGGAGGAGGAGAGGCAUUCUGAUUUUUGGAAUUUUCAGCCUUUUUGCACUGGUUUUUCCUCAUCUUUAUGGAUUUAUGUACCUUUGGUCUUUGAUGUUGGUGACCUUCAGAAGGGGUUUUUGUGUGGUCGUUCUUUUUUUGGAUGUUAUGCUAUUCUUCUGUUUGUUCUAACAGGCCCCUCUGCUGCAGGUCUGCUGGAGUUUGCUGGAGGUCCACUCCAGACCCUGUUUGCCUGGGUAUCACCAGCGGAGGCUGCAGAACAGCAAGGAUUGCUGUCUGUUCCUUCCUCUGGAAGCUUCAUCCCACCAUAUGCCAGCCGGAGCUCUCCUGUAUGAGGUGUCUAUCAACCCCUGCUGGGAGAUGCUCCCAGUCAGGAGGCACAGGGUCAGGGACUCACUUGAGGAGGUAGUCUGUCCCUUAGCAGAGCUCAAGUGCUGUGCUGGGAGAUCUGCUGCUCUCUUCAGAGCCAGCAGGCAGGAACAUUUAAUUCUGCUGAAGCUGCACCCACAGCCACCCCUUCCCCCAGGUGCUAUGUCCCAGGGAGAUGGGAGUUUGAUCUAUAAGCCCCUGACUGGGGCUGCUGCCUUUCUUUCAGAGAUGCCCUGCCCAGAGAGGAGGAAUUUAGAGAGGCAGUCUGGCUACCUCAGCUUUGCUAAGCUGUGGUGGUCUCCACCCAGUUUGAACUUCCCGGCAUCUUUGUUAAUCCUGUGAAGGGAGAACUGCCUACUCAAGCCUCAGUAAUGGCGGACACCCUUCCCCCCACCAAGCUGGAGCAUCCCAGGUCAACUUCAUACUGCUCUGCUAGCAGUGAGAAUUUCAAGCCAAUGGAUCUUAGCUUGCUGGGCUCCAUGGGGGUGGGAUCCACUGAGCUAGACCACUUGGCUCCCUGGCUUCAGCCCCUUUUCCAGGGGAUUGAACGGUUUUGUCUCACUGGCAUUCCAGGUGCCACUGGGGUAUGAAAAGAAACUCCUGCAGCUAGCUCGUUGUCUGCCCAAACAGCCGCCCAGUUUUGUGCUUGGAACUUAGGCCCUGGUGGCAUAGGCACUCUAGGGAAUCUCCUGGUCUGCAGGUUGUGAAGACCAUGGGAAAAGUGUAGUAUCUGGGCCGGAAUGCACCAUUCCUCACAACACAGUCCCUCAUGGCUUCCCUUGGCUAGGGGAGGGAGUUCUUCAACCCCUUGGGCUUCCCAGAUGAGAUGCCCCACCUGACUUCGGCUCACCCUCCAUAGGCUGCACCCACUGUCUAACCAGUUCCAGUGAGAUAAGCUGGGUACCAAAGUUGGAAAUGCAGAAAUCGCCCACCUUCUGCAUUGAUCUCACUGGGAGAAUCACUUGAACCCAGGAGGCAGAAGUUGUGGUGAGCUGAGAUUGCACCAUUACACUCCAGCCCGGACAACAAGAGCGAAACUCCGUCUCAAAAAAAAAAAAGAGAGAAAACAAGUUUUCUAGGGUGAAACUUUUAAUUUUGUUUCUAGACAAAUAAUUUUGAAUAUCUGCCACAUAUCCACAUUUCUGACCCAUUUCUGCUGGAUUUGAAGGUAAAAGAAAAGAGCAAAAGGUGAGUCUAAGGACUGGCUUGACUCCAGAUAAAUAUCUUCCUCAGUUAUGCGGUCAGAUCUGUAGGAGAAUGCUGCGUCUUAGCAGUAUGGGAAACUAACUUGGCCUAGUCUGGUGAUGGCAGUAAAACUUUUAACAAUUCAUCAGCCCUUUUAAUGCCAGUUUUUUAUAUAAUACCCUUCACUUAUAUUCAGCCACUCAGCACUUGCCAUGUGCCAGGUUCUAUACUAGGUGCUAAGGACACAACCUUCACAACAAGUACAGCCCCUGCUCUUGAAAAGUAAAGGCCCAAAAAAUGUAAGUUAGCCAUUCCAGGUCAGUGAGAGUAAAAUUAUGUGUAGGGGAUGAGGGUGGUGGCACAGAAAUUGUUUUGAGUUCCAAGCAAAGGCAAGAGAAUAUGUGGUACAUUUGACAACCGAAAAAAAGUCCGGUAUUGCUGGAGAAUAGAGUAUGAGGGUAGGACAAUAAAAAGAAAUAACCCUAGAGAAAUAAGCAGGAGCCAGGUCAUGGAGAGCUUUCUCAGCCUUGUAAAAACUUGGAAAAGGGAUUCUAAGAAAGGGAAUAUAAUAUGAUUAGAUUUGAAUUUUUCAGUGAACAGUCUAGCUGUGAUAAGGGUAAUGGAUUAAGAGAGUUACAGGACUAAAAGCAAGGCUGGUUAAAUCAUGAUGACCUGGAUGAGGCAGUGGAGAUGGAAAAAAUCAUUUGAUGUGAGAGCUAUUUAGGAAACUCAGUGGGUCCUGAAUAUUGAUCAGCUUUCAUGGGUAAUAGGGCAGAAGCAUCAGUUUGGUGUCCAGGCUUUUGGUUUGGGCAAUUGUGUGGAUGCCUCUCAUUAACAGAGAAAAUAUUUUUAGGAGAAUGAUGAGUUCAGUUUUGGCAUGCUGAGUUUGAGGUGCCUGCAAAACCUCCAAGUAGAAAUGGACACUAAACUAUUAAAUAUAUUGGCUGAGGCUCGGGAGAGAGAUUAUUAUAUAAAUAAACACAAUUUUUUAAAAAGAAAAGGAAAUGACUAUGAAGGAGAAAGGAAAACUUUUGAAACAACUGGAAGAAAAGGAGGAAUCAACAGAGGUUUUAGUUUAUUUGUUUAAGAUGAAAGAGACCUGAAUGAUUAUAAAUUGUAUAAAUAGCUAGUCCGAAUGUGAAGAUGCAGAUAAUUAGGCUAUAGAAUGGAAAUGCGUUUGAAGAUAAGGCAGGAUUUGAUUGAGAGCUUAAUUUGGGAGAAAAUUUGCCUUUAGAAAGAAGGAGCACGAGCCUAAUGCUGACAGGUCUUCAGAUUUGGUAGUGAAAAGUUAAAGAAUGGCCAGGCGCGGUGGCUUACGCCUGUAAUCCCAGCACUUUAGGAGGCCGAGGCAGGUGGAUCACCUAAGGUCAGAGGUUUGAGACCAGCCUGGCCAACAUGGUGAAACCCUGUCUCUACUAAAAAUACAAAAAUUAGCCAGGUAUGGUGGCGCACGCCUGUAUUCCCAGCUACUUGGGAGGCUGAGGCAGGAGAAUCACUUGAACCCAGGAGAUGGAGGUUUCAGUGAGCCAAGAUCAUGCCACUGCACUCCAGCCUGGGUGACAGAGCAAGACUCUAUCUCAAAGAAAAAAAAAAAAGAAUAGAAAAGAAAAGUUAAAGAAUUCCAUUCUGAUAAAUUUUGGUUUUGCCUGGAAGUAGGAGACCAGGUGAAGAAAGAAAAGGGAAGAUUGCAAUCUGAGGUUUAAAAAGUGAAGAAUGUAAGUUAGGCUUCGUUUUACAAAUAAAAAUAUCUACAUUUUUUAUUUUAAAAUGGCCAUUCUAAAAAAAAUUCAAGUGAUGAAAUUAAAUUCCCUAAGCAUACCACCCCUGAGAAAUAAUCUGUUUCUAUUAAUAGCAGUGUGCACAGACUUCCAAAUAAACAGACUCAUAUGCACAUUGUCCUAUAACUUGAUUUUCCUUUUAUUGCUUUUUUCCAAUUAUAAAAAUAAUACGUUCUAUUUACCAAAAAAAUGUACAUAUUGCCUAUUUUAGUUUGGAUAUUUUUCAUGUAGUAGUAUGUAGAUACAACUUUCUUCUUUUUAGCAACCAUAUUGCAUUUAAUUAAUUGACUAUGCCACCAUUGGACAGUAUCUAUUGAAAGUUACUCAUUUUUCUUCCUUUUUUGGCUAAUAUUAACAGUUUUGAAGUAAGUAUCUUUGUACAUUUUUGCUAGUGUUUCUGUAAAAUAAAUUUCAAAAAGUGAAAUUUCUAGGUCAAAAGGUAAACAUGUAUUUAGUUUGGAAAAUUAUAGCCAAAUUGUUCUGCAAAAUAGUUAUACAAGUUUACAUUUAUGUCUUAAGUGUUAUUUUAAUCUUUGUUAUUCUGCAAAAAAUCAAUUAAAUUUGUAUUUAUUUGGUAAGCAGUGAGGUUGAGCAUAUUUUUAUUAAUUAUUGACCAUUUAUAUUUAUCUCAUACAUUACCAGGUCUUUCUUGUCAAUUGAGUCUUUGUCAAUUCUUUAUUGAUUAGUAGGAGUUCUUUAUAUAUGAUGGAUAAUAGUCCUUAUUGUAUGUGGUACAUUUUUGCCUAGUUGCCUUUUUAUCUUUUUGCUUUGCUUAUGGAGUUUGUUAAGGUUUUUUUCUAAGCCAACGUUUUUCGUUUUUAUGUAGCCAAAAAUGCAGUUUUUUUUUAGUUUCCACUCUUAUUGUCAUGCCAUAAGUCCCUCCCCACAAUUAUGCAUAUGUUCUCUUUUAUUUUCUUUUAGUGCCUUUAUGAUUUUUUUUUAACUUUUAAAUGAUAACAUUUGGAGAGUUGUCUAGAAUUACGUAGUACAAUGGCUGAACAAUGUUGAGGGCUGAGUUGUGGUUGAUGAUGAUUUGUUUGUAGGAGCAACAAUCUGUUAGCCAGGGACAAGCCAGUCAGCUGGGUUUAUCCAACCUUGGAGUGUUUCAGGCAAGUACCUUAAAUGGACAGUGGGGCCUAGCAGAUUAGGAAAACACAAUGAAAUGUUGGACCAUGAUCUUCCAGCAAAGGUUGAGAAGUGAAAACAAAACAAGGGCUAAUAGGAAGAAAGGAAAGGAUAAAUGGACUGGAAGCCGUAAAGAUUUUUUUUAAGGUAAGAAAGGGAAUUAUUUUAGUAAGAUGGUUAAAAAGAUAGGAGGUUGUGGUCAAAUUGGGGGAAUGUCUAAAUUUAUUGUUUCAAAAGAAUGCUGCAAUGUCCAGAGUAAAAUGUCAAGAACAGGCAGGUGAAAUAGACUGGAAGAAAGGGGCAUUGUAGAUCAAGGAAUCUAGCAGUCAGACCCUUGGAUAGGUUAUUCAUGGGAAUGUUGAAGACUCCCAGGAUUACAGUUGGACUUGAGUAGAAAGAAGCAUCUUUUGAAUAUCUGAGACUUCUUUCACCAACACCUUUGUCAACCUUUAUUUAUUUUUGAGAGACUCAUCCCCAGUUACUAAAGAAUAAAAAGUCAGUUUAUCAAAAAAUGUGAAUGAAGUCAGAAUCAGAAUAAUACCACCCUCCCCACCUCCACUUGCUUCUGGAAAAAUAUUUGUGUUUGGGUUCUUUUUUAAUAUGUGAUAGCAGCUAAUAAUAUAUGUAAAGCACUUAGCUGAUGCCUAACACAUAGUCAGUACAUUUUUGCCUUUAUUAUAUUAGAGGGAGAUGAUUUAUAUAUGCUUUAAAAUUGGUAUUUGUUUAGUAUUUCUUUCAAGUUAAGAUUUGGAAUUUUGGCAGCCUUGGUCCAGAAUAAAUGACCAGGCAGCUUCAACAUGAACUUGUUUCUAGAACCCCAGAAGGGUUGGGAAUACAUAUAAGAAGCCCAUACUCAAGGCCUGGGAAAGUAGAAAGAGGCAAGGAAGGAGAGAAGAAAAUAGAAAGAAGUUGGAUUAGAUAGAUGAGCAAAUACUGGUUAGUUCUGUUUCCUCUCACCUUGACACAUGUGUCCAUUCAGUCACCAAGACAUGAGAAGCAGUAAAUCCUGGGUGAGGCUUAAGCACCCUCUGGUUAUUUUGUAGUGAACAAACUAACAGCUAAGAUUUUUUAGAACCACUCACUUAGAGAAUCAGCUUUUAGAACUUGCAGUUCUUUUUUUCAGUACAUUGGUGGGAAAUGUCAUGGGGAAGAGGAAGGGCUUGUGAAUAUUUUAUAAGAUUUUUAACUUUUUUUCAGUCUGGAAAAUACAGUGGAAAUGGAAAAUAAUUGUACAAAGAAUGUAAACAAGUAAAUGGAGGAAUUUAAGAUUAUUAUCAGAGUCUUUUAUCCUUCCUUUCUUCACCCACUCAAAUUAAUUAUUCAUUACUUAUGUUGUCUUUAAAAAGAGAAAACCUAAAUUCUUUGCUGCUAAAGUUUACAUUGAUUUUAUAAAUUUAAAAAAACUAAUAUAAGCCUUAAAUAUAACCAGGCUAUUUUAUAAUCUGAUAGCAUCUUUGCAGAGUGAAGCUCAAAAUAAAUUAGAAAACAUAUCAGUACUCUUUAAUAUAGGACAUUUCUGAUGAGAAAUAUUACAAACAUGAGAUCUAAAAGGAUGUAAGUCAUUGAUGAAUUAAAUACCUCAGAGCCAUAUGACCUGAGACUUAUUUCUGUUGUCUGCUCACAAUGAGGCACUUUACAGAAAUAUAACUCUUUAGUUGCUACUUGCACAAUUUCAACUGAAGUUUUAAAUUAGAAGGUGUAAAAGCAAUGAUCCUCACUAUAACACUUCAACGUACAGCAAUAUUGUAACAAAUAUAAAUGCUACAAACUGGUUUGUUAAGAUAAAGUAGUUAAAUAUCAUGAGAGUGGCACUGUUUACCCCCUCUUUAGUCUGUGGUCAUUUGUUUUAAUUUUUACCUAUGUGACUUGGUUGCUAACUAGGAUGUUUUUUAGUACAAAUGAUGCAAACAUCUGUGUUACAUAUACCAGAAAUUCAAAAAGGAAAUAAAAAGAACUCUAUUCUCCAAGGGACUGUGUGACUGGAUCUCUUAAAAACAGAUUCAAAUAAAUAAAACUCAAUCACACUAACUUUAAGUUGUGCUUUAAAAUUUUUUACUAUUUGUCUGAAUCCUGACAAAAUGUAUACUGAGGGUAGCAAAACAUAUUUGUGUAUACAGGUAAGCUACACUUCAUUGAUUCAUUUCUCUAUUUAACAAAUUUUUAUUGAGCAUAUGUUAUGUGCUUAAAACAGGAGAUAAGUAGUAAACAAGAAAAAUGAAGAAGAUAGUGAUGAUGUUGAUAAUGAUAAUAACAGCUAGCCUGUAUUGAGUGCUACCCAUGUGUCAGGUAUUUAUGUCGAUUAAUCCUCACGUAACAAUAUGAGUCAGAUUCUAAUAUCAUUCCACUUUGCAAGUGAGGGAAUAGAUUUAGAGAGCUCUCACAGCUAGGAAAUAAUGCAGCCUGACUCAAACACUGCAAUUCUGACUCCCAGGGCCAGAUUCCUAACUAACAACAUGCAAAUACAUUCAUUUUCCUCAUGGAGCAUAUGUUCCAGCUACCCAUUUAUUUAACAAAUAUGUAUCAAGUGUCUGCUAUGUGCCAGGCACAGUCCUAGGCCCUGAGUUACAGAGAAAAAGAGUUUGACACGGUCAUUGCUAUCAUGGCUUACACCUUCCAGAGCCUCUAAUAGAGGUUUUGUAAAAAGGGAGAAAGUAUGCACGUAUUAAUGCAAGUACUAGACAUAAUUAAAGUAAUUAAUAACAUUGACAAGAAUUACUAAACUAUUGAAAUAUAAUACAGUUUCUUUAAAAAUACAUACUGUAUAUUCAGAAAGGGUAAUGUUAUUUUUACAUCUUAAAAAGAAUUCAUUUUCAUCUCUGGUUCAAAAUAUAUAUCUUUAAAAAAAAAACUUUUUGCCUGGUGUGAUUCCGUCCUGCGCGGCUGUUCUCUGCAGCAGCGUUGUUUUAUCUCCGUCCGCCUUCUCUCCUACCUAAGUGCGUGCCGCCACCCGAUGGAAGAUUCGAUGGACAUGGACAUGAGCCCCCUGAGGCCCCAGAACUAUCUUUUCGGUUGUGAACUAAAGGCCGACAAAGAUGAUCACUUUAAGGUGGAUAAUGAUGAAAAUGAGCGCCAGUUAUCCUUAAGAACGGCCAGUUUAGGGCUGGUGCAAAGGAUGAACUGCACAUUGUUGAAGCAGAGGCCAUGAAUUACGAAGGCAGUCCAAUUAAAGUAACACUGGCAACUUUGAAAAUGUCUGUACAGCCAACAGUUUCCCUUGGGGGCUUUGAAAUAACACCACCAGUGGUCUUAAGGUUGAAGUGUGGUUCAGGGCCAGUGCAUAUUAGUGGACAGCACUUAGUAGCUGUGGAGGAAGAUGCAGAGUCAGAAGAUGAAGAGGAGGAGGAUGUGAAACUCUGAAGUAUAUCUGGAAAGCGGUCUGCCCCUGGAGGUGGUAGCAAGGUUCCACAGAAAAAAGUAAAACUUGCUGCUGAUGAAGAUGAUGACGAUGAUGAUGAAGAGGAUGAUGAUGAAGAUGAUGAUGAUGAUGAUUUUGAUGAUGAGGAAGCUGAAGAAAAAGCGCCAGUGAAGAAAUCUAUACGAGAUACUCCAGCCAAAAA